ACAACACAGCUAACACAAGGCCCCGCAGGCAGGACUCUGGGACAGACGCAGGCCAGCUGCCCAGAGCCCAGACCAAGCAUGGACGCCGUGGAUGCCACCAUGGAGAAACUCCGGGCACAGUGCCUGUCCCGCGGGGCCUCGGGCAUCCAGGGCCUGGCCAGGUUUUUCCGCCAACUAGACCGGGACGGGAGCAGAUCCCUGGACGCUGAUGAGUUCCGGCAGGGUCUGGCCAAACUCGGGCUGGUGCUGGACCAGGCGGAGGCAGAGGGUGUGUGCAGGAAGUGGGACCGCAAUGGCAGCGGGACGCUGGAUCUGGAGGAGUUCCUUCGGGCGCUGCGGCCCCCCAUGUCCCAGGCCCGGGAGGCUGUCAUCGCAGCUGCAUUUGCCAAGCUGGACCGCAGUGGGGACGGCGUCGUGACGGUGGACGACCUCCGCGGGGUGUACAGUGGCCGUGCCCACCCCAAGGUGCGCAGUGGGGAGUGGACCGAGGACGAGGUGCUGCGCCGCUUCCUGGACAACUUCGACUCCUCUGAGAAGGACGGGCAGGUCACACUGGCGGAAUUCCAGGACUACUACAGCGGCGUGAGUGCCUCCAUGAACACGGAUGAGGAGUUCGUGGCCAUGAUGACCAGUGCCUGGCAGCUGUGAGCAGCUCCGGCUCAGCCCUGCUGCCCUGGCCUGUCACUCCCCACCCCUGCCGGAGACCUCCCUUCCCUGGGCCCCUUCUCUCCUGGGCAGCCACACCACAGAGCGGGGAGGGGCAGGUGGGGGAAUGGAGGCUGCAGGACUGGCUAGACCAGGUCCCUGCCGGUCCACCAGGCGGAGGUGGGACAAAGGUCCUAACAGGAGUCACUGGCUCAGGACCCCAGGGAGAAACGCUCUCCCCACCCACGCCAUGCUGACCAGAGAUCUUGCAGCCCCUGUGGAUGCCCCCGCCGAGGUCCCCCGAUCCCCGCACCCGGACUGCUGCUCCCUGCCCCUCCCUUGCGGGUCCCCCAGGAAGCCAGGUGACCCCAGGUGGGAGGCUGUGUGUGGAGGCCAUCCUGGAAGGAAGUUUAGACCUGCCCAGGUGUGGAGCGAGGGGCACAGGGGCAUCCUAACCUCAGAAACUGAAAUAAAGCCUUUGAAAAAAAAAUCUGUAAAACAUCAACCCCCAAUCAGAAGAUGGCAAAUGGGGAAUAAAAAUAGCAGGUAACAUGUCCAGCGGGCCCAGUAUCUACAUUCUGGUGAGCGGCCCGAGGCUGGGAGCUCUGGGCGGGGGCAGACCGGCGGGGCCUUGCAGCAGGGGUGGGGGUAAAGUGCGGGUGGUGGUGGAGAGAACAGGGCUGUGGCUGGACCCCAGCACUGGUGACACGCUGGGUGGGAGCAUGAGGCCCCAGGCUGCUGGAGGUCCUCGCCCGGGGAGGUGGAGGCCGUUCCUGGUCAGGGGCUUCCUGAGGCCCCUGGGGCAUGCAGAGGCCAGGGUUUUAGUUAAAAGUUUAAUGUAGUUCCCAAAUACAUUUCAUAUGACAAUCUUACAUAAAUGUUCCAAAACACA